CAACCAGCAGACUGAAAAUAUUCAAGACAAAAAAAUAAAAGAUAACUAUUACAAAUAAAAUAAUAGAGUAUAACAACUAUUUACAUCGCAUUUACUUUGAAUUAGGAAUUACAAGUAAUUUAGAGAGGAUUUAGAGUACCCGAGAGGUAUGCAUCCCUGGAUUUUGGUAUCUGCGGGUUUUGAUACAGGGGUGACCUGGAACCAAUCGCCCCAUGCACGCUGCCAGGUGAUGACUGUAAAUGGUCCUCUGAAUCAGUGACUCGCUGAGGGAAUCAGGAAGAACAAUCUUACCUUUCUGCUCAAGCUCAGGCUCACAGUUUAAUCUUUUAACCUCCCUCUGCAUCAGUCUAAGUUUCAAAUAAUAAUGGUAAUUUAUUUCCUCUGUUAUUAAAAAACAAGACCAAAAAAACCACAAACAAAACCCUAUCAAGACUGGUGGGGUAUGACCUGUAUAUUUUUAGCUUCUGAAAUUUGUCCUAUUACUAUUUAAAAUUAAAAGAAUACAUUUUUCUAUUUAUAAAUAUAUUUAAGACUGCCAAAUGAUAGCUGUUCCUUACCCAACAUUAGUUAUAAAGAAAAAAAGCAAUUCCAAACAAAAAUGAUAUUGCAACAAAAACAUGAUAUAUGUAUUUUGUGAAAGAAGUACAGCUGCCUCAGAGACAAUGAGAGGCUAUGAAAAUAAAGGAAAACCAUCUGAGCUCUGGUUAGAGACUCUGGAAGUAGUGAGCACAAAUUUCUUUGAAAGAAAAAGAAGAGGAGUCUGAUGUAGGUAGACAAUCCAAUUCUAGUUACUGUCUUUAUUUGUGAUAGUCCAUAGUCUAAAAAGGUGCAAAUACUAUUAACUAGCCUGAGGACAAGGUGGCAACUGCAUUUCAUUCUGAAAUGGAAAAAUCCAAGGAAGGUAGAAGAAACAAUUGCAUGAGAAUUAUUACUCAAUUAUUUUUCCUCAAAAAGCUGUGUAUCUUCUUUUUUGAACUUUGGGAAAGCAUAUAUAAGAGUUUCUUUGACCCCGAAUAGUCCAUGUAUUUACCCAGAAAUAUUUGUGUAUCUUGCUACUGCAGCAGGAUUACAAAAUAGAUUACAACUCUACUGUAGAAAGAAAAUAUGUUUUUAUAUAAUCUGUAACUUAUCUGGGUAGCUAGAAAACAUACACACACACACACACACACACACACACACACACACACACACACACACACUACAUUUUAAUCCUGGCAUCUCAGUCAACUCCCAUAUCUGAGUGGUUCUUUCAAAUAAUGCUUCUGAGUCUACAACUUUACCUUUCCUUCUCUAAGAAGUGUCAGGGCAUAUGGCUGGAGGAACUUAGUAUAUAGACCUAGAUAGAGCUCAGGGUUUUGGGGACCAGUUAUGAAGGGGCUGAGGGAUCUAUAGGCCACUUCCUUUGAUAAACCUCUGUACCAGCUCUUUUCUUCCCAAAAUUUCCCCAAGUAACAAGGUUUAGUUUAGUUUUUUUUUUUUUUAAGCUUCUUACUCAUAAGCUUCUUUCAUGGCAAACCCUGAUAUUUUUUUCCUAGGUAGAAAAUUAUUUGGAUUUAUCCAUCUAAUUCUCUGAUACAGUAAAAGAUAGCUAUAAACUUUUAGCAAAAUUUAUCUCUAUGAAGAUUUUAGACUUUGAAGCUUAACUGACUAAAUUUUUCCAAUACUUGCUCUCUAUUGUCUGAAGGGUAGACAUUUCCUUGCCUUUAAGAGGUGGAAAGCCACAAGGGAACAAGUCCUUAAAGAGAUAGUCUAAAAAGCCCUUUCUAAUCUACACCACCUCCAGCACCACCAAAAGUCUUCAAUUUUAUCCACAUAUUUGUUUCUAUGCGAUAACCGAUAUAUUUUUGAGUUACUUUAUUUCCCAACCCCCUCUCCGUCCCACCCCCCACCGCCAACAACUAGAGUGCAAAUUCCAUGAGAUCAGGGUCUUGGCUUUUUAUUAUUUUUUCAUUGCAGGACCUACCUACAAUAAUUACUGGCACAUAGGAGCCACUCACUAAAUACUUCUAGAAUGAAAGAAAAUAAAAAUGUGAUGCAUCCUUACAGUAGAUUAUCCACUGCAAAUUUUGGUUGCUAGCAAGCAUGCAUCUUUUGUGCUACUGCCUCAAAUGGGCCUUCUGCUGCAGACAUACUUAUCUAUUGACAGUUCUUUUGAACCACCAUUGCUCUUCAUGUUUUCUUGCUUUAAAUCAUGCUGUUGCCGCUGCCUAGAAGGUUCACUUGUGAACCUUCUUGUCUUUCACACUCCUAAAUUUCCUCAAAACAUAAAUCAGGUGUCCUGGUCUCCAAAAGUAUUUCAUGAUAAACUUUUUCUUUCUCUAAGUCCCUGUGCUGACAUAUAACCCUCAUACCCUAUGCUGGCCCUAAACUUGUUCUUUCUCUACGUCCCUGUGCUGACAUAUAACCCCCAUACCCUAUGCUGGCUCUUAACUCACUCUUUAUACUAUUCUCUCUGAUGGAAACUCAUGGACUUUGUUAAGGGAGGCAUUGAAAGCAGGAACUGUUUGCUAUUUCUGGCAUCAAAAGCAAAAUGCCUGGUGCAUGACAACUAUUCAUAAACAUUGAAUAAAUGAACAACAACCCACCUUAUUUCUCUCUCAUGGUACUACUCUUUAUUGUUUUAAACUUCUAUAGUUAUCCUGGGGAAAUAUGAGAGUAAUGAGUUUUCUUGAAAGUCAGGUGCAGGGACAUUUAUGGCAAUACUUGUCUUGAAGAUCAACUACAUCAAAGUUUCAAGACUAACUAGAAUAAUUCUCAAGGAGAAGGAAAGAGGCAUUCAAGCUUAUUUUGGAGUAGUAAAUAACAGUGAUUCUGGUGUCCAAACUGUCACAAAGACAACCACUGCCAUAUUAAGCUUCUAAUACUAAGAAAAGUGUCAGGUAUACGGUAGUAGAUCCUGAUGAAACUCUUCAGAAACUGUUUCUGCACUUUACCUCAUCUGGCAGCUCUUGGUGUGCGCUGAGGUAAUAUAUUAAAUUUGUGGUGUAAUUAGUUUAGAAAUUAUUCCCCUAGGGAACAAAGAUGGUCAAGAGACAAAGCUUGAUCUAAAGUUGACAGCCUGGGAGACAGGCCGAAUUUGGAGGUGUUACCGUAGCAUAUGUGGCUUAGUAUUGAAUAGGUCAAAAUAUUAAUGACCCAUCCUACACACAACCCAGGGAAAAAUGACUGGGCAUUGUGAGAGAGUGUGGGUGUCUUGGCAGAAAGGUAUUACAUCUGUUUCUUCCACAUCUAUGAGUGAAUUAUGCAUGCUAUGACAAGGAGGCUUUUUUAAAUAUGAGAAAUUUGAGGCAAAAAUGAUAGACCAAAAAAGUGCAGAGAAACAAGGUGAGUAAUGAAAGGCAGAAGUGGUAUAUUGGCAGGCCUGGAAAUCAGCUGUGAGUAAUUUGAGUUAAUUAAAUGUGGCAUAAAACAUUUGGAGGAAAAGGUUGAUGAGAUCCAAUUAAUGGGCAAAAGAAAUAAUUUUCUGAACAGUAACAUUUGGGCUAUAUCAAAGAUAAAAGUGGUAUGUGAUAAGAGAUUGAGAAAAUGAACAUGAUAAUUCUUUUGUCACAUGAGGAAAUCUGAGGUGAGGCUGAGAACCCUGUCUCGAUGUAAGGAAGAAAUCAUCUUCAGGAAAUGGCAGUUGCAUAAAACAAAAAGGGAGACUCAGGGGUAUAAGCAAGUGGAUUAAAAACUUGUCUGAUUUAUUCAUAAAUGAUCUGACUCCAUUUACUUCUGUUUCUCAGAUUUCUUGGGAAUUGAUAAGUAUAUUUUCUCCAUAGUACUUCUUGAGAUGUAGAACAUCUAACAUCAAUACUGAUUAUUGAGUUUUGUUGUUUUUCUCUAACUCAGAGAUUUUUAUUUUAAAGCAGCAGUAAGCAAUCUAUAAUUCACAGCAGUAAACUAUAAUCUACAAGCCAAACCCAUUCUUAGCUAAGAAUGCUUUUUACAUUUUUAAAAGGUAAAAAAAGGAAAAAAAAUGAAGAAUAUGUGAUUAUGUAGUCCACAAGGACAAAAAUAUUUAUUACCUGCAGUGCUUAAAUUUAAAGGGUAAAAUUAAUUAAAGAAAUCCUCACAUUAGAAUUACAUGUAAUAUAAUUAUAUGUAAUAAACCUAAUUAUAUUACAUAUAAUGCAUGAUCCUCUACGAAUUUAAUUUGAAUGUGAAGAUUUCUCUAAUUGCAUAUAUAUAAACAUACACCUACAGUUUUAUGUGAGAGAACAAUUCUGUCUUACACAUUAUAUGAUUUCACACCUUUGAGGAUAGAUUGCUAGAUAAAAGAGAUAGGAAAAAAUAUUUAGCAGUUUCAUAGUUCAUUGGGGUCAAGAAGAAAGAGGAGUGUGGCAAGUUCAUUUUCUUCUUACAAUUACAACAUCAGAGAAGAAAUGAAGUAAAAAAAAAAAAAAGUGAAUCAGAAGCCUGAUUGUAGGAGAUGCAUGGAGAGAAUGAAUAAGGCAAUAAAAGGGUGUAACUUGCUUCCCUACGAGUUCUAAUGCUAGGAGGAAAACGAAAAAUAAAAAUAUAGGUCUCGAGGGUGCCAGCUCCACUGCCCCCCUGCUACCCCUGCCCCUAGCAAGUAUUAGGGAGGGUAAGAACUCUAUCUGCUAAGCUUUUGCUGUCUUCUCAAAAGAGAUAUUGUAUAGAUAGUCCCUCAAAUAGACAUAAAUAUAUAUCCACAUCUAUUUUGGAUGGUAGUAUUUAGCUUCUUAUGAUUGUGUGUAUAAAGCACUUCAAGCAUGCUGCUCCUAGUCAAAUCCCUGCAGGGCCAAACAAAUUGGGGCAGUUCAAAGCCAAGAGAGAUGGGAGAGGCUGUGACAUACUGGGAAUAGAUUGUGCUCUUCCUAAAAGGAUUAAAAUUAUAUUAAAUUAACAGCAAAGAAUAUAAAGCAGUCAGAAGUCACCAGUUGCAACUCCUGCUCUUUUUCCUGUGAACCGUUCCCCUUUUUCAGGUAGAGGGACAGAGGGGGUGGGGCAGGGACUUCUUUCAGUUGUUACUUUCUGGUUUUCCUUUUUUCGCAAAUUUUUUUUUUUUAGACAUUCUGUAUGUGUUCAUAAAAGUCACACAUAUGUAUACUCUAAUUACAAUGAUUCCAUCUACAAAAAUCUGUAUUACAUAUAAUUAUUACAUUUUAUAAUUAUUACAUUUGAGAAAAAUUAGUUUUCUUCCCAAAGGAGGCCUAUAUAACUUUAAUCUAUUAAAAUAAAAUUAAUUUUGAAUAGCACAUUAACCAGAUGUUUUGCUAAGCUAUUUCUGGAUAAUUCCAAACUAAAUUGGCAAAUUUUAUUUAUUUUUAAUUGACAAAAUUAUAUAUAUACAAGGUACAUUUACAAAAUUUUAAAACAGUUGUUACCUUCUUGAAACUAUUUAUUCUAAUUUUAUUCUAAUUCAAUUCAGCCCAACCUCAACAUCUCUGCAUUUCCCCUAUGAAUCCAUCUACUAUCAUCGUCUACUCUCCAAAUUCUUCCUGAUAAAUAAUAUUCUUAUAUUUUUUAAGCAGUUAAAUUUAUACCACUUACUAUUUAUCAGUGGCAUUUAACUCUCACAAGUAUUAUCCACAUUUUACAAAUAAAAGUUGCACAGUUGGCAAGUGGCAAUCUAGAAUUCAGACCCAAAGGCUUCAACCCAAUGGGUCAUGCUCUUAAUCAUGAAGCUAAACCCACCUCAAAGAAGUAUGAGGGAAAUGAAAGGCAGAUACUGGAUCCCAUAUAUACAACAGCUGUCAGGUGGAAAUAUCUGACAGAAAUGUAUUUCCACUGAACUCUUUUAUUUCUCUAACCAUUGAAUUAAGCAAUAGCACAUCCUUAUUAAACAUGAUCUCUCUUUAAACUUUUGAUUAUUUCAUAAAUUUACAUAUAUAUAGUAAUGUGAACUUUUGUUAAAACAUUGCAAAAUAUCAGUUGAAUUGUAUUUCAAAUAAAUAUAUCACUUUCCUCAAUGUUGACUUAAUGUGCACUACUGUUCAUAUUUUUCUGGAUAGUCCACAAUUAUUCAAAUGGUAAUUAAAGUGUCAAAACCAUGUUUCAACACUUGUUUUUAUGUCCAUGCUCCUAACAAAACAGCCCUCUUUGUUCUUCACAUUUUCUGGCUUCUUCAGCUCAACUGAAAUUUGGAUUUCUCUUUUUUUUUUUUUUUUUUAGAUUCCCUCUACCAUCUCCAACAGAAGGUUAGCUUUCUCUUUCAAGAGUAUAAGAGGCAGGGGCUGGGUGUGGUGGUUCAGACCUGUAAUCCCAACACUUUGGGAGACCAAGGUGGGUGGAUUACUUGAGCCCAGGAGUUCAAGACCAGCCUGGACACCAUAGUAAGACCCUAUCUCUACAAAAAAUAUAUUUUAAAAAAUCAGCUGGGCAUGGUGGUGUGCAUCUGUAGUCCCGUCUACUCAAGAUGAUUGCUUGAGCCUGAAAGAUAGAAGAUGCAGUGAGCCAUGAUGGCACCACUGCACUUCAGCCUAGGCUACAGAGCAAGACCCUGUCUCAAAAAAUACAGUAAGAAGAGCCAUGCCACUCCUUGUAUUUAUGCCACUUUGUUUUUGCUUCUACUACCAUACUGCACUGCCCUAGUUUGAACUUAAUGUUAGGAAGUACUAUGGCCCUCUCUCUGUUCAGGCCACUUCCUAUUCACCCCAGAACCAGUGUCCAUUUGUAGUCAACUACAGUUCACCAAGCUUUCUAUUAUUUCUUUAGCUCCAGCACCUAUAUUCAUCUAUCUCAUAACUUCAUAUGUCAUCCACAUCUCAAAAUUCAAACUUCUAAACUCCACUGCAACAAUAAGAGAUCAAAUGAGCUUAUGUGAGGUGAUCAGAAAUUAAGAUAUUGUAAACGUCAGAAAUGUAAAAGGCCAACCACUAUCUGUUCUGCAAAUUAAUAUAUUGUUAAUACUAAAAUUUGUAGUCCCAGCAUAUGUUUGCUUUUUUUCCAGAAUUUGCUGUAUCUCUAUCAUAUGCUAGGCACUGAUUAUUUGGUUUCAUUUUUCUUCCUAUUAAAUAGUGACAAUUUUUUUUAAUUUGUUUUCCAGACAGAAUGACAGCUUGACAAAAAGAUGUUGUGGUGUGUACCAAAUACCAAGAUGCCCCUCCUACCUGUACUCUCUUUUGUAUUCCCAGUCAUACCACCAUAGUUUAGAUUCUAUUUUUUAUUUCAACUUUUACAAAAGUGUCUUAUCUCCUUCCUGUCUCGUAUCCAUCUGAAGAUGAAGAGUGUUGGGCUCUUCCUUCAGGGGAAGGCUGUCACCACCUGCUGAAUUAUGCCCAAGAUUUCAGCAGCGAGAACUUCCUCCUUCAGAAAUGAAGAGAACCAACACAGGAAGUAGCAUGAAGAUGUGCCAUAGAAUUAAAGCAAGGUGAUGCUUAAUGAAUCUUUCAGUGCCCUCUCAGAAAUGUACACGCAAAUAUACGUGUGCCCAAGAUUUUCAGUGUAAUUUCAAAGGGAUUCUCAGAACUCUACAUGCCUUGAACACUGAGGUCAGAACCCUGGUUCCAGAUAUUUUAAGAUUUGCUUUUAAAUAAUGCAACCCAGAGAGCUGUGUGCUUGGAUCAAAUUGUUCAGAUUCCUUGUAGCAUUGCUUCUAAGUGUCCCACCCUAUGCCUUUGACUUGCAUUAAUGGGCAAAUUGUAAGUUUCUUUUCUGUCUUUUGACAGAGGUCAUCAUCCAUCAUAUCCUUCGUAUGUGGUCUGUAUAAAUGCACACAAUGUCUUACAUAUUAUUUCACCAGGCUAACAGAUACCUGGAGUACAAACUAAAGUUUCAGGGACUCCAGGCUAGCAAUCUUCUAAAAGGAAUAAACUAGCUUUUAUAAAACAGACCUUAUUUUUCUCAUACUCUGUUUUUUCUAGUUAUUCUCUUAUUUUCCCAUCAAUUCUUUAAUGUUUCAACUAUAUCAUAUGUACUGAAGUGAAAUAAUGCAACAUCCUUUGUUCACACCUAAACCCAGGCAUUAACGUGGAGGCCUAGAGGCUGGUAUGGUGGUGCCAGUGAUAAUCAAAACGAGAAUUCCUAAAUGGAUGCAGUUUUCCUCCGUCACCUACCUGGAGAUUGUUUUCCAAUGCUAAAAUCAGGCCAGUUUCAAUUUUGCUUUAACUAAGAGAAUUGGUGUUUUCUUUCAUUGUUACUUUGUUUUCUCUAAAAUUACGAUGUCGUGUUGCUGCCCAUUGAAUAUAUCCAGAGUAUACUCCGUAUCCUGGCACUUCAGGCAUUUCUACUGUUCCAACCUAUGGCUGCAGCUCCGUUAUUUCCAAUUUCCCUAAUCAUAGGCCUGUGCUGCUGUCGAACUCCACAAGUCUCCUUUCAAGCACUGGGAAGUUUCUGAUCUUUGUGGCACUUUUCAUGCUAUUAACUAUGCCAGGAAUUUGAUGUUCUCACAUGCAAUGCAUAUUAAAACCCAUUUACUAUAAUAUACUUAUAUAGCUAAUAAAUCAGACAAAAAUUAUUAAAUGACACUUAAGGAUUGCUAUGCUGUUAUACAAUGUAGAUGUAUACUACCUUCUACCUCGUGGCAAACAAGUGCCUUCAUGUUUUUGCUCCAACUUACUUCAACAGCCUCAUGUCUUCUAACACUUAACUUUAAAUUCUGUGUUCUCACAGUACUUGAAAUUUCAAUGUGCUUUGCUCUAUAUUUUCUAGGCCAUUGCAUGUGGUACUCUCUUUGCCUGAAGUUCUCUUUUUCCUCCAUACUUCACCUGCCCACCACCCUUUCUCCCUGUAAUGGGCCACAAUCUACUUUGGGAAAGGCUGGUUUCUGUCCUUCUCAUGGGUUCACCUAACAUCCUAUUCUGAAUCAUAUUCCAGCACACUAUAUUUUGAAAUUCCCUGUUUGUUGUCUUAUUGCACUGUUUCCAGUGCCUACACUGCACCUAGCACAUGGAAAACACUUGAGUGAAUGUUGCUGACAUUGAAAUAUAGGUAUUACUGGUUUUGAAGAGCUAUUUGAUAAAAGUAAUUGAAAGCCAUAAAAAUACUUUUCAUCUAUUAAUCCAGGAAUCAAAAACUUAAAUGCUUUCAGAGGUCAGGCAGGUCAUGUAAAUGUCCAGUGUAGUACAGAAGAUAACAACAGAGAGUACAGACUAAUGUACGUACCUUAUCUAAACACAUUCAGAUUCACAUUUUUAUAAUUACUGUCCAAGCCAAACAAAUUAUAACCCCGUCUUCAAAUAAUUUCUUAGAAGGAAAAAAAGAUAUAUUUAUUAAAAUGUUACCUGCAGAUUUAUUUGUAAUAAGGAAAAAGUAAAUACACAUUAAAUAGCCAGUAAUAGAGGCCUGAUUAAAUAUGGAUUAUAUCCAUUAUAUGUCAUAUAUUCUUUAUUAUUAAAGAAUCUCCCAAACGGUAAUAUAUGGAAAAUGCUUUCACUAUUGGAAAUAAUAAAGAAAAAAGCUAAAUUACAUGCUUUCUAUAAUUGCAACUAAGUAAACAUAUGCUUCCUUAUUAAAAUGAAAAGAAAGGAUUAUGCAAAAUGAAAAUACCUAUAAUAGGGUGCUCAAAAUAGAAAUGAUUUUUUUAAAAAUUCAACAUUUAGUAAUGCUUUUGUUUUUCCAACCCCAGUCUUUGGAGAAAAUGUUGGGACUAUCUUUUGGAAUCUUAGAAUUUGACACCUAGCAAGCAAAAUCAUGUUACUUUGGGUAAGAGCUGAAGAAUAUCAGUUGUGGGCUGAGAUAGAAAUACCAUUGUCAUGGCAACCACCAAAAAUUUCAUAGAAAAGGCAUAGCUUGGAUUUUUUUUAAUGGAGAUGACUAACAAGAUUGCUUUUGAAAUAGUUCUGAUAUAGUGUGGGAUAAUAUACAGUAACUCCGAUAAACAGUUUUGCUGGAAAAUUGAGAUAAAGUGGCAUAACCUUAAGAUCAGAACUUAGAAUCCCUAGUGUAAGCUUAGCAUAUUUUGUAUACUAAUUAGCUUUUACUGACAUAAUACUAAUAUGAUACCAGUCUGUCUUCCCUGAAUACAAAAAUUACAUAUUUAGUAACAUUAUAAUUCUAUAAUGAUAAUAAUUCUCAUCAAUAAAAGAGCUUGGGUUUUCUUGUCAAGGGAGAUUUAAAGUAUUUUUCUGAUUCUUUAUGAAGACUCAAUUAUGUGUUUUCACUGUUCCUCUAUGAUACUAUAUAUAACCUACUGGAAACAGAAGCUUGUGGAAAUACUGAUAGCAUCAAUAGAAAUCAUCGUGACUCCUUCCUUGGAAAGGGCAUGUUUCAUCAGUACCGUUUGCCUCAUUUAUUAAGCUGAAUUGUCAUCUUAAGUGACAGAUAUUUUCAAUGUCCAAACUUCCUGCAAAGAUUUAUGUAUUUUAUCCCAUUCUGUUUGAAUUUAGAUCAAGAAUGCUCAUUAGAUUAUUUUGUGAGCCCAGGUUUGCUAGAGUUUACAAAAUCUGACCUAGCUCACUAGCCACAGAGAGGCUAUCUUCAUACAAUGAAGGUUUCCUGAAGAGUGAAUGAAAUCCAUGGCUUUGUCGAAUACAUCAACUAAUACAUUGAAACUGCUAAUUGUGUGAUUGUCCUGGGGACAUGACUAGUUUAUUUGGAAACUACUUGUAAAAUCUGCUUUGCCUUGCAAAAUUGCUUCCCCUGAGAAAUUGCUUCUUCAAUGGCAUAUCCAGUGGAGACCUUUCGGUAUCUUGCACAAUUAGUCAGCCUAGAUAUAGGACCAUAUAGUUAAGAAGGAAGAGACAGACGGUCAGUAAUUACAAUUUUAAAUUAUAAUUACAAAAUUGUAAUUAUUUUAAGGGUGAAAUUCUAAUUGGCAUUUUUUGUUUCAUGUAAACUUCUGUAGAGCUGCAUUUAUCAUAAAUAGCCACAUAUCCAAAGUAUCACAUUUCUCAUGUCACAUACAAACUUUUGACUCUAGCAUUCAAUGUAACGUUAAAAAAAAUCAAAUCCUAUUACCUCAAAAUAAGGGCUGUGUGCCAGGAUUGGGAAGCAUUACAAAAUGAGUUAAAAUUAAAUGAGAUGUGGAGCGGAGUUUGAAACCCAUGCCGUUAAAACCUCAUAACUGAAAUUGGCACCUGAUUGUUUUUCAUUCAGCUCUCGAACCAGUUAAAUAGAUGCCAUAAAUAUGUUGAUUCUUGUAACCCGUUUAGUCUAUUUAUUGUUUUCUGAAGCCACCAGUAAAACUAGUCUUUUUCACCAGCUACUGAAGACAGAGGUCAUGUUAUAAAUCAAAUGGAAUUAUUAACUUCUGUUUCCAUUUUUAAGCAUUUGACCACAAAAUUAAACCUUGUAUUUCUACAUAAAAAUCCAAGCAUUAUAAUGUGAAUGAGAUCUGUCCACUCAUUCAUUCAACACCCACUUACUAAAAUGCUAUUUCAAAGACUAUUCUAAUAAGUUAAAAACUGUUUGAGGAUCUUACUGUCUAGUUAGUCAUACAGUUAAUCAUCACAAAUACUGAAGGUUUGAAUCAGAAAAGAAAAAAGAGAAAAAACAAAAACAGUUUUGUUUUUUUUUGUUUGUUUGUUUUUUUGUGAUUGGAGUCUCGCUCUGUCGCCAGGCUGGAGUGCAAUGGCAACAUCUCGGCUCAAUGCAACCUCUGCCUCCCAGGUUCAAGCAACUCUCCUGCCUCAGCCUCCCAAGUAGCUGGGAUUAUAGGCGCCACCACACCCGGCUAAUUUUUGUUUUUUUAUUAGAGACGGGGUUUCACCAUAUUAGCCAAGAUGGUCUUGAUCUCUUGACCUCGUGAUCCACCCACCUCAGCCUCCCAAAGUGCUGGGAUUACAGGCGUGAGCCACCGCACCUGGCCUUACCAGUAUUUUUAAAAUGUUGCACACAAAUAGCCAUAAAUAGCACAGGGGUAGGACUUUUUCCAUUGAAAAAUAUAUGACUUCUCUAUAAUUAAUUUAUAUAUCUUAACCACUUAUGUUACAAAUGAGGAAAAUAUAAAUCUACCAAAAUCAUUCUGUAAAACCAUUCCUGCUUUGAGUCAUAUGAAUACUUGUUGCUAAUUUGAGGCUUUCUAAAUUUAAAGACAUAAGAUGAGUAGUUAAUGACUUUGAAAUUUAAUUAGGAAAGUGGUGACUGAGAGAGGACUAGACAGUAUGUUGUUUGCACUAAUUUGAUUUAUAUAACCCUUUUCUAGUCAACCUUUUAAAAAUCAGCCAGAGAGUAGAAAUUCUCCACCUUCAAAAAUUAGGAGGUUUACUAAUUUUUGAAUCUGGGUGAAGUUUCCCAGAUUAAUCCAAAUGCAACUAAAAUGUGAUGAAAGAUGAAGCUCAUCUUAGUUUUCUUAAUCUACAUGACCUACUUUGUCCAGUUACUUAAAUUCAGAAUUUUCAUGUUCACAGUUUGAACCAGGAGAAGUACCUCUCUAGGUUCACUUUUCUCUGAAAUUCUAAGACUAAAUAAAAUAUUAAUAAAAUGUCUCAAUAAUUAUCUCACAAAUAUAUUAAGAUAAAUAGUAUGAAAUAAGUUUUAAAAAAUAUUAGAAUAACAGUAUUAUUAGAAAAUAUAUCUUAAAAGGGAUUAAACUACACAGAUAUAAGGUUUGAUGUAUUUUCUUAAAAGAUGAGAACUUACUACCAGAAACAUGUAGUAUAUUAAUAGCCUCAUUAUGGAGGUGAGAUUCUCUCUUUAGCAGAACACAAUUAGGGAAUAUGUGAGUGAUGUUUUAUUUUUUAUACAUUGCCUUAUUAUGCAUUUCCAGUCAUGAUCUCCUAGUGUAAUUGCAUUUAAAUUGUGUUCUUAACCAUAUGUUAAUUAAAUAAACUCAAUGUAAAGACCCAAUCUAACUUUCCUUAGUAAUGUGGAGUUAAUAAAAACUGCAGCUCAUUGGAAUCUAGAGUAUUACAGGAUCUUUGCAUACCUAGCUCUUAAACUGAUUUGUUUUGGAUUCCGGAAAACUUAGCACCUUGGUUAAGUGGCUUGUGAAGAAAUUUUGAUACAUACAUCCACCUCACGUAGAUCUAAUAGCUAUGUGUUUGGAAAGUAUUUUGUGGAAACAAAGAAUUAAACAGCAAGGAAAUUUGGUUUUCCUUAAGAACACUGAAUCGUAUAGAGAUAGGAUAAUUUCUGGAGACAAAUAGGCCUGUCAAUAAAGGUCAAAUAUAUGCAACUCCCUCCUUUUGCUGAAAAUCUGUUAUUCCAUGUUGACUUAGAUAUUAAGAGAAUACUAUACUUUCCAAUAAUUAUAUUGUUAUAAUGCAGGGGAUAUAGUUCCCACCAGUGACUCUACAUCUACAAUAUAUGAUGAAAUAAAAGAUAUAAUUAUAAAAUAUCAUACUAUCAUACUCAAUUCAUUGAGAUAAUAAAGUACAUUCUAAACCUUAUUUAAUGGACAAAUACAUGCACUAUCAGGUGGUUACAUGAAUCUCCAUUAUAUUUGAAAAAGGUAUAUGUGUUGACAUUAAAACCACAUUUCUACGGUGUCUUAAAUUAUAACUACACAAAAUUAACACACUAACUCUGUCACUUAUUUACACCAAUAAAAGUCUGUUUCCAAACAAGAAAGCUGCACUGGGUAUAUGUAUAUGGGUGUUUAUGUGAUUUAGAUGACUGGCAUAUUUUUAAAAACUGUCCAAAGGAGUUUGAAGUCAUAAUUUUAAUGUAGCAGGAAAAGAUAAAGUCAUUCUCCCAUAUUUCCUUAAUGUUCAGAUGCUAUGUGUUGUAUGACAUGAUGUAUAUAAUGUAAGUUACUAAAACUUUUUUUGGAAGAGAAAAAGCUAGAGUAGCAGAUAUGCACACUAAAAGGCAAAAAUCUGGUUUUACAAGUUUUAUAAUAAAAAAGGUGGCAAGAUGAACGUUUUUUUAACUUAGAACUAAAUUUAAGCUUAACUUUUACAGCAAUCUUUAGAAAAUUUUGCUAUAUGGUCUUUCUUGAAGAUUAUUUGUAAUUUUGUAUAAUUGAUUUAGAAAUUCCCAUCAAAUUUUAAAAUUCAGAGUUCUAGAUAAAACCAUCAAUUAUCUGAAAUCCUUUCUCAGUCAAGACUGCCCAUGAAGCCAAGUGCCUUAUUUGAUCCUAUAAGCUUCACUGAAAAUCAGCAGAGUCUUUAUUAAUUUAUAAAUGAUGGGCAUGAUUAACUGGUCUCAAGUUUGCUCACAAUUCUGAACCCUUGAAAUCACUGAAAUACCAAAAAAAAAAAAAAAAAGUAAGAAUAAAGCUAUUAGGAAAAGCGAUUACUUGAGCCUACUCAGAGUCUCAGUGAAACAAAGGUCCAUUUUGUGCAUAAGUGUAAAGAAAUAUAUUUUUGAAAAAAUUGUAUUUACAAUUAGAAAAUGAACUCUGAGGUUUCAUUUAUUGCUAGUCAAAGAGUUUAGAGCCAUUGUAAAUAGUUUCCUCUAGACCGUAAUACAAUGAGUUUAUUUUAGUCAGCAAUUACAAUGACAAAAUGCUAGGUAUCAUUGAGUAGAACAUUAGGCAAAGAUCCGUUUCUUCCUCUUGUAUAAAAUCUGAAUGCAUUCUAUUAAAGAACAGAAUUAAACAGGCAAGCAAAGAUGUAUUCAAGACUAUUUCAAUAGGGGAGAAAGACUGAACUCAAUUCUGCUGAAAUAAAAGGGAGGCAAGUUUUUAAAUGAUGCUGUGAGCUAGUGAAAAAUACUGGAGGAUAUUAGGGUAGAGUUUGUCAAUGUGAUUAGACAUUUGUGUUUGCUAAUGGGUGCUUAGCCAAGUUAGGGUCCUAUCCUUCGUGCAGUUUGGGAAAUAGGAACAUUAUUAUCUUUCUUGAUUAUUACAUUUCAAAAAGAUGGUUCCCAGGUCUAUCAGAAAGACAUUCUUGGGUUGUAAAAUAUUUACAGCUCAAAGAGUCAGAGAAAGAAUUUACAAUUCCAAGUUUUCUAAAGUAAGUGAUCUUGAAAAAGGGUGGUUAGAGGCCUAGGGUCCCAGAAGGAAGAAACCUGCCGGCAGUUCAUCAAGCUAAGUGGGAACUUUAAGGCUGUCUUGAUCAAUCCAAACCUGGAACACAGAUUCAGAUCUGAUUGCCAAUGCAAGAAAAAAGCUUGAAAAGACAGACACUCCCCUGAUCACCCAUCCUCCCUUAUCUGAGUUAAAUAUUUCAUUUAUUUAUGUUUUUUUAAUUUUUUCAUAGGUUUUUGGGAGAACAUGUGGUAUUUGGUUACAUGAGUAUAUUCUUUAGUGGUGAUUUGUGAGAUUUUGGUGCACCCAUUACCCAAGCAGUAUACGCUGAACCCAAUUUGUAGCCUUUUAUCCUUCACCCCCUUCCCACCCUUUCUCCCUCAAGACCCCAAAGUUCAUUGUAUCAUUCUUAUGCCUUUGCAUCCUCAUAGCUUAGCUCCCACUUAUGCGUGAGAACAUACGAUGUUUGGUUUAUGUGUUACUAUGGAGGCACAGGAUUGCCAAUGUCACAGAUUUUAUCUGGAUGAAUUGCAAGUUUUUGUCUGUUUAUUACUCUUGACAAGAGACUAUGAAGUUUAUGAGGGCAAGAAUCUUGUGUGUUUGUAAUCUCAGGAUUUACAGUAAUGCCCCUCACCUCAUAGUAAUUCAAUUAAUACUUGACUGAAUUUUAAAGAUUUCAGAGAAUAAGAUAAGAAAUAAGGAUAUGGGAAUAAGAGUGUGGAUAUUACAAAAGAAGAGUCUUUAGUUUGGUAAUAUGAAUGCUAUAAAGGAAUAUGAUCAGAGACAUGUUCCUGGAGGUAUGAACUGUUCUAGUAAAUCCUAGACAACUAAAAGUGGGCCAUACCCAGUGAAGAUAGGAAAAGGAGCUUAUGUCUAAUGUAUGGUAUAUGGUAGACACCAUGUUAGCAUAUCUAAAUAGUCCUUCGUCUGGAAGAAAAGUAUUACAGGCUCCACUUCAUAAGUGCAGAAACUGACAGAGUAGCCAUAUAGCUACACUCACCCUCACCUCUGUUGCCCAGUUAUAAAGCCAUUAGACUUUGUUGCUGUAAACUUAAACUGUAAUCGUUUAAUUUUUAGAGAAUAGAAGAAACAGAACUUUUAACUUUACAUAUUAGAUGACACCCCCAAGAAAGGAUCAUCCACAAAAUAAAAAUAGAAUCUAUGCAGUAUUAGAUAUAUAUUUAAAUGCUAGAGACAGGGAAGGAUAAAAAUGGCUAAUGUUUUGGGGUACCUUCCAAAACAUCUGAAGGGAGUGUCAACACAAGGAGAAUCUGUUUCUUGGCAGAACCUUCAGCAAUUAAAUUCUGGUUUGGAUGGUCAUUGAGAUGGAAGUUAGUGGGGCUCUUCCCGGUAUUUAAAACAUUCUCUGUGAUUCUUUGCUAAUGAAAUAUCUCUGUUUCCUUGGUUUUAUUAUCACUGGAAAGACGUUUAAGGGAACAAUCUUUCUGUGUUUUUCAGAUGUGCAUUGAGAAUGCUGUUUAACUCCUAUUAUGUGCUGGAGAGGUAUUGAUAGUUCCUGUAUAUGUCUCUGUAUGUCAGGACAAGAAAUAUUAAAGCUGCUUGGUGCCAUUCCUAUCUGGUUAAAAAAAAUUAUAAAGGAAGAUAUUCCUGAAUUGAAGGGAGAUGUCUGGAACAAGAGCAAGCAAAGUGGAGAGAAUUUAAUUAACAAUUUAGUUCAAUCUGAAAGUCCCAUAAAAUUCAAAUACCCAUGUUGGGCUGAUAUGAUACUUAUUUUCAAAACAAUAUGGCUUGAAACUUUUUCUAAAGAAUUUGUGGUGAGAAAAAAAACUAAUGGUAAUCUACUGAAUAAAAGAAAUAUCUAUUUUUCUAACAAUUCUUUGAAAUCCUUGACUUGUCAUUUGACCGAUUUUACCAUUUUCUUAAAAAAAAAAAAAAAAAGGAAGUUGCAUACUGGAAGGAAGGAAGACUUAGUGCUUUUCUGGUGCACUGUUGGCAUUCUUCCAAUUCUUCUGGAAAACAUCAUUCUAUCAUUUAUGCUCCCGUGAGUCAAAAUGAAAAAGUCUGUAUAGCCUCUUAGACAGAAGUAUCAGGAUAUUCUUAAAGGGGCCUUAUCCAAACAGGCAUAUUUAAAAUAGUUAUUAGUUUAUCAUUAAGCCCUAACAAGACUGCAAAGUUGCUUAGCAACAGAAUCAGGCACCCUUAACAGGAACAUGCAUGGGAACAAUGGUGAAACAUAAUUGAGCCUUAAAAAGGCAAAUUCUUUGAAUUAAAUCGUGAAAAGACAAUGUGUCAUGGGAAGAAUGAGUAUUUUAACCUAAGACUUGUUCUCUAAGCAUUAUUUUAUAGCUAGACCUAAGUGUCUUUCCAUAGAAUAAAUAAUGAUACUUUUAGUCUUUAUAUAAUUUAAGGCACUUAAAAAAGAUUGUUUAUCCAAGUUAGCUCAACAAUGCAUAAUAUCUCUAUUUUGACCCAUUAAUUAUCUUCAACAUUGUAGAGAUACAUAAAGAAAGGAAGGCUCUUACAAAAAUAAACACUACAAAAUAUUUGAUGACUGCAAGGGUUUAAUUUUGAUGUUAUGUAUAAUUUAAACUAUCAGAAACUCAAAAACUGUACUUUUAUUUUUUAAAUUUGAAUAUACAUUUACAUAUACACACAUAACGUAUCUAAUUCCCAUUUGCAGGAAAAAAAAAAAAAAAAGCCUGAAAAGCACUGUCUCUUUUAGAGUUCUUUUGACUAGUUUGACAUUGGCUGACUUUAUACUCCAGUACCCGUAAAAGCACUGUCUUGCUUCAUUUAGUAAUAAUGGAAACAAAUCUGGUGCAUGUGGGCUGUCUUGAUAUAAUGCAUAAACACCUAAAAAGUUCAGUCAGGGAAUAAACUCAGGGUCCCGUCUGUGGAGGCAGAGAAUCCCGGCUUGGAUCCUAGUCCUAUUUCUGGCUUUAUCAAAUCACUUACCCACUCUAGACCUCAUACUCCUCAUCUAUAAAAUAAGACUUCUAAGAUCCCUUCACAUCUAAUAAUUCUAUGUCCAUCAACUCUUAAGUGGUGUCAUUCUUUUUUUCUCAUAGAAGAAUUGUUUGUUUUAUUGAAUUGGUUAUUUGACUGCUGUCUCUUAUGUAAAUACUAGAAGUAGUAGGCCUAUUUACCAACACUGUUAGAAUAUUAGGCAGAAAAAAUUCCCUACUGGCUUCUUUUUGGCUUUCCUUUAUGUCUGAUUAUAUGUUGCACUGCCAAUUUUUGGUCCCUGAAAGCUGAAAACGUGCAGAUGCAGACAGAUGUAAUAUGCCGCAGCUUUUUGUAUCAAGCCACUCUAUUUUAAAACAACUGGAUUUUUUUUUUUUUUUUGCAGUCUUUGGAAGAGGGUUAGAUGACCAAAUCUAUUUUCCUUUUCUUCAGAGUUUUAUAACACCACAAAAGGUCAUCCUUAAACAGUCAGAUAAGAUUAACAACAAAAUCUUGGAAAACAGCCAGUGCAUCAACAAAACAAACCCAGUGGACUGUUUAUAAAUGUUAAGUUUAAACAGGCAGCAGAACACGGGAUGGGGAGGAGAGGAGAGAUACUUCAUAGACAUAGCAAAGAAAUAAUUUCCAGAGAUGACCCAUGACACUGCAGUGUUGGGAACCAAUAUCAACAAACAAACUUGACACCCAGCAAUAUGUAGAGUGCAUUUAUAAAGAUGUUAGAAGGAGCAAGUCGUAGAUCACAAGUCACAGAAGCAGAAUCAUGGGCCAUUCCCAUACUGGGUUCUUCAUGCCAUUUUUAAUGAAAAGAUAAAUUGGUGGAAAUAUUUUAAUUGCAAAGAAGUGAAAAAGUGAUUUUUAAUGCCACCAGUUGACGCCAGGCCAGGGUUUUCACUAUGCAACCUAGCAUGUAGCCCUAAAGUCCUGACAGCUAAAUAGUAGGGAAGACACUGUUCUCUUCCUUGCAAAUACCACUUCCUUUACUAAGGAUUCUAAAGGAAGAGAAAGCUUUUAACAGAGAACACCUGAGAGGAAAGCCACCAAUAUUUAAAUCCAGGAACUUAAUAUUGACCUAAGGAGCAAGUAGGCUUAGGUAAAGGGCAAGCUAAGAAAUUGUUGAAGGCCUUGCACAUUUAGUUAAAAUUUUUAAAAUUCUGAAUAGAAAUAGAGAAUUCCCUGCAAAUUGUAUUUUAUCCAUGAUUCAGAUGUGGCCUGUUAGAAGUUUACCAGGAUGAAAAGUAAGCUGCUGAGGAUUGCAGAUGAUACUAAUACAGACAUAAUAACAAGCAGAGACUGAUAUUUGUAACAAAGGAUUUCACCAGCUUUCUAAGAAAGGCUUUCAUGGUUGACACAAGAAUUAGAUUGUAGUUAUACCUGAUAUGAAUUUUAGAUUAUGCAAUACAUAAAGAUGCAUUUAGGAGACAUUCUCAAUAAAUUGCACAUCAUAUAUUGCAGUAGUAAAUGUUACAUUCUUUUCAAUGAAUAACUUUACAGUAUUUUGUGGUUUAAAGAGACUAGUUUAAAAAUAAAAGAUUGUUUUAAAUUUGAGAAAUGAGCAAGUUAAAAUAAGAUGAACCAGAUUUCUACAAUCCACUUUCUGAUGCUCAAAGUGGAGAGGGUACAAAAUGGUGCAUGACUGAGUCUAUGGCAAUCUGCGUUUUCUGCACUGUGUGAAUCAUAUUAUACAUUCUGUAAUAUGAAGGGGUACAAGGCACUUACAGGUUGCAUUUUUCAAACUUUUACAAAGGAAUAGUAGUCACCUUCAGAGACUUCUCUUCUAACUAAUUAGACCUUAGACAAACAUAUAUUUGCAUAAGUUUCAUCAAGCUGCACUUUCUGAAUUUCUUUCUCCCUUGAGUCUAUUUAUUACUCAAUUCACUCUGUUAUCUAAUACCCCUUACAGUAACUGUAUGCCCUGAAAUUCUCUUCCCUCCUCCACAUCAUCAAAACUUGCUUUUGGAUCAUUCAGACUGAGGUAAAAAAAAAAUGACUAAGAUCUUAAAGUACAGAUAUUUGAAUUUCAAUAGAAAAGAAAGGCUAAAGGAUUGAGGUUCUCAGGCAAAGAGACAAGAGUCUGCUAGGCAUCAGAACUUUUUGGCUUCUCCCAGUUACAAGACUCAUCUUAUAAGCCAUAUAGUUGGAGAGAAGUAGUCAUUCAAAAGGCUCAAAAUAUAGGAAAACAAAAAUAAAAAUCACUUCUUAGUUCAUAAAUACAAUGUAGGUCUAUUGAAGAGAACAUUAAAAUUGAUCCCUGUUUUCUGAUCUCAAACUGGCCAACAGUGAGAAGGAGUUGGAUAAAGCAGCCUUGGUGUUGGUGAAUGCAAGAAGAAUUGAGUGUAUAAUUACAAAAGGAAAGUGAGUGUCAAUGUGUGUGUGUGAGAGAGUGUUUGUAUAGAAACCACUCUAGAAAAAGACAUUUAAAACUGCUAAAGUUAUUAAUGCACUGAAAAGAAACUAUUAACUUCAAAAUCAUUCUAUUGCUAUAUUAAGUCAUAUUUGAGGGACAAAUCAAUAGCAAUGACUUUCUUGAAAUGUCUCCCAACACUAUGAUUUUGUUUUAUGGCACUGGUGGGUAAAGGGGUUUGGUCUGAAAGGACACAAACAGGUAAUACUAUCAGUUAAGAAUGUUGGCAGUAGUUGAGCAAAAAAAUAAAAUAUGAUAGAAAGCACAGUUUGUUUCCUUUGUCCUUUCCUUUUAUGUUUAGCAGUUAUGUAAAUUAAAAGAAAUUGAUCUUACUACCUAUUCUUUUUAUUCAGUUACCAAAAGAACAUUUGCUUUGAAUGAAUAUGGAUGCAUUUUUCUUUUAACAGAAUCAGGCAGCCAAACAUGACUCACUGUUAUUUACAUGAGUCAGUAUCUACUUGCCCAUGUAAUCUUGUUUCACUAACUUUACAGUCAGAUCAUUCUUGUUACGAUCAGGGAAAAUGCAAGCAAGAAUAAAUGUGAUGCCAAUUAAUACAACUACGAAUUAGUAUUUAGUAGUAGUUAUUGAUCAUUUUAUAUGGGAAGUAAAAAAAUCAAUUAUCUAACAUUCCAUUGUUUACUAUUAUUUUUAACAAAAAUGGGAUUUUGUUUUUUUUUACACAAUGUUCUGUUCUUUGUUAAGAAGUGAGGAAAAAAGCACUUACUGAUCCUAAGCAAGUCAGCUCCUCGAUUUGCCUGAUGACGAUGAAUAUGAAUACAGGCUUUCUCUCCAGUACAGUUGCUCUUCAUCAAAAACAGGCUGGCUCUAACAUAUUUCACAAACACAGAAAAGUGUGCCAAGACACAGUCAGCAAUUCUUUUUAAUUUUUGAGAUUUAAAAUAUUACUGAACUUUGUUUGAGUUUUACAUUUCUCAUGGAUAAUUUUACUGUGAAAUUUAUGAUGCUAUAAAACUAUGUUUAUGAAGAUACUAUAGUAGGUUUCACAUAUCUCCAUAUCUUAUAUUGGUAACAUUUAAAUUUGAAUACUACAUCUUUAUCCUUUCAUAAACUAGAAGAUAAUUGUUCUGAUGACUAGCAGAAGAAGCUGGCAGGAACGAUAGAUUUGCCACUCUUUGCUUUCUGUUAUUUGUGAGUCUAAUUACUCUAGUUGGUCAAUUAAUGGCAACACAUGACAAAAUCUUCCUACUAAUUGACUCUCACUAUUUUGUUACUGCUGAAGCUUCCUCUAAUUUUGUAUGUGCAUAUGUUACCCUACUUGUCAUUUUUUUCCUCCUAACCUUCCUUAUCAGAAAGCCCAUCUCACCAACUUCACAGUCAGAUAAUUCUUGUUAUGAUCAGGAAAAAAGCAAACAAGAAUGAAUGUGACGCCAAUUAAUAUAAUUACUAAUUAGAAGCCACAUUUUGAGGGCAUUAAAACAGAAGAAGAGUAGAAAUGAUAAUAACUUGGUUUUAGGGAAGCUGUUAACAUAUAAAUAGAACCCAAAAUGGCACCACUGGUAGUUUUCCAGGGACUUAAUAUUUCUGACACACACUCAAUUUGUGCCCAUGGAUAAGACAUACUAUAUUAUAGGAGAAUCAAAGAGUUACAUAUUUGGAAAAAUCAGGUUACCAAAAAGAAUAAUGACAUUGUUUAAACAAUAAUGCAUUAAACUUUCCUUGUUUAUUAUGCUAGAAGUUGUAUGAGAUUAUCUGAGUAAAAGCAUUUCAAUUACUUCAGCAUUGUGGGACAUGAAGUGUAAAAGAACUCAGAACAUGGGAAAAAAAGGAAAAAGAGAAAGGAAAUGGCUGAAAGAUUAAUUACUUGGCUGUCAGCUGCUAGGGGAGUUUAUUUAUGUUCUCUUAAUAUUCAUAAGGCUCUUGUCAAAAUGGUAUUAUUAAAUACCCAUUUUAUAGAAAAGGGACUGAGGCUGUUCAACUGCAGUUUAUUUGAUGGGUAUUUAUGCCUGUGAUGGGGACAGCUAUGUCAGGAACUUCAAUUCCAGUUAAAGUGAAACCUGGCAGAGACAUAGUUUUGAUCCAAAUUUUGACAGUAGUACAAUGUUGCUUGUCCUUCUCCGGGAUGGUAGUCUGUGUUUCCCUGUAACAUUUUGUCUGAUUUGUUUGUACCAACUAUUUGGUUUUGUAAAUUUAUGUGACACUUUGUUUUAAGCUAAUUAUAAAUGUAAAUUAGACUCUAAGAUGUCUUUUUUCCACUAACUGGUUUUGUAGUAGCAAAAAUCUGAAAUUACAUGCAAAAUGCUGUUUACAGUUGUUUUAGUAAGGGGAUGCAGAGCAGUCAGAGUGAGUUGUCAGAUUCUCAAAACAAAAUCAAAUUAUCUAAUAUUUUACAUUAAAUCAGGUAAUGAAUACCGCUUCUGGAUCCAAACAUUGGUUUAAUUAUUUAUAAUCUUUGCAGUGUCCCUAAAAUAUCUAUUAUCUCCAAUUAACACUAAGGAAACUGAGGCAUAGAGAGGUCCAAGUAAGUGGCAGGGAUGGAAUUCAAACCCAGGUCAGUUUCAGGCUUGAACUCCACUAAUUCUAUACCUUUCACUGCCUCUCUCACUGUAGGUAAUUGUAUUAGUCUGUUUUCAUGCUGCUGAUAAAGAUAUACCCGAGUCUGGGAAGAAAAAGAGGCUUAAUUGGACUUACAAUUCUACAUGGCUGGGGAGGCCUCAGAAUCAUGGUGGGAGGCAAAAAGCACUCCUUUCAUGGCAGCGGCAAGAGACGAUGAGGAAGAAGCAAAAGCGGAAACUCCUGAUAAACUCAUCAGAUCUCGUGAGAGAUUGGGAGUGUGCUUUUGAGGAAGACCACAGAGAUAAAGGGCCAUUUUGUCAAGAUGACUUAUCACUGCUGAUGUCAACCUUGAUCACCUGGCUGAGAUAGUCGUCAUCAUCAGUUUCCUGACUUUCUGAGAAGCCCUGGUUUCCCCAAAGAAGUGAUUUCUGAUAGAAAUCUGAAGGUCAUCUCCAAGAAAAAAGAGAUCUAGUAUAGUCAAUGAAUUAAAGACAAGAAGGUUUCCAAUCAGUCCCUGCUAUGUGGAUAUUUGGUAGCAAUGACUGAUGUGGAAACUACAUAUGCAGAUUUUAUUGCUUCAGGAAGAACAGGUAGAAGAAAUGCAAUACAUGAUAUCCUGGUUUCCUCUGCAAGUGGCAACAGCAAUGAAUUAGCCUUGAAAUUAGCAGGUCUUGAUAUCAACAAGACAGAAGGUGAAGAAGAUGCACAACGAAGUUCUACAGAACAAAGUGGGGAAGCCCAGGGAGAAGCAGCAAAAUCUGAAAGCUAACACCCCACUUUGACCCUCGACCACACCUGAAAAUGUCUCAAAUCUCCAGGAGUAUCUGGAAUGCAUUUGUUUCCAUGAGUGAAAAGAGGAAAAAGAAAAUGGCUGUGCUGCAUUGCAGGAACCUGCUCAUUAUCAUGUUAAAAAUGAGGGCAGAGGCUGUGGCUGCAGGCAGACUUUUCCCUACCUCUGUCAUUAGCAAUGGUUGAAAUCAUGUGGCUUGUGUUUGGGCGUCAUUUUUGUAUGGAUCCUUUCACUUGAUCAUAUGACGAAAUGCUUAUAGAGAGUAGCUCCGACCUAGAUGAUGAUUCUUCCUGUAGCAUCUGGCCCCUCACAAUGUCAGAGGAUUUAAUUGUGUCUAAUUGCGAAGGGUUGAUUGAACCCCAGAGUUUAAAUAUCUCUGGCUCAAGUGUUCACCCAGUAAAAGAAAGAUCCAGAAAGCACUGUUUUUAGCAUUACGUAUCUGUGUGUUACUGCUGUGUUAUUUACACUGUUUUGUAUUGUACAAUAUAUAUGCUCAGCACUGCCCCCUUCUCUGAUUGCUUAUGAAAAACAAAAUGAUGUACAUUACUGUGAAUUUUUAUACCACUCAUUUUUAAAAGGGCUGUCUUUUCAUUUUAGUUUUCCAUACUGUGGUGGUGUACACAGGAUAGAACACCCUUUUUUAAAACACAGUCUUUCCCCUUGCUCAUUGUAUGUUGAUGAGUUGAUUAAGUCUAACAGAUUCAUCAAGACUCCAUUGCUUUAUUAUAGAGACAUUUGAAAAUAUCCAUUAAUGUGAAUAUCACCUGAAUUCAGUCUGUUUGGUGUCUGCACAGACUGGAAUUCAAUCUGUCAAAUUUGUUUUAUUCUCAAGUGGAGAACUUCUCCCACAUAAUAUAUAUAUAUAUAUAUAUUUUAAUUUAUGAGAAUUUUGGACAAUUGGAAAGGUAGAAAAGAAAAGCCAAGAUCAUACUAAGGACUGGAAAUAUUUUGUUCUAUGGAAUCAAAUUUCUCACAAUGCUGUAUGAUACUAUUUAAAUUUGGAGGACAACUUAUCUUCACUAAGCUGAAUCAGGUGGAGAAAGUAAUCUCCUUGCAAUCAUGUGGACACCAAUCACAAAAGUAAAGCCCUGGUGUUGUGUUUUCAUGUCUUUUUUCAGCCCUCUCAGAUCCAAAUGUUAUUAUGCACUUUUUAAUGUUUGUAAACUUUUACUAAUAAUUAGUGUGAAUUGCAUUCUGAUACAAUAAUGAUUAUCAUUAGAAGCUAACAAAAUUCUCAUUAAUACUGUGUUUGAUGGCCUCUGCUGUGUUUUAACAUCGUGCUUCUUAUAUGGAAAGUUUUUGUGAGCUGUGUAAUCCCUCUGGUCAGUAUUAUGAAAUCAUUUGUCAGUGGUAAUAAAUAAGGAACCAGUAAUAUGCCAAUGGUUCAUGAAUUACUGGACAAAUAGCAGACAAUGGGAGUCCCUUUACAAUAACGAGCCCACUUAGCUGUCCUUGAGGGCUUAGAUACCUUGCCACGUGAAGUAGGUAGAGCAGCAUUUCAAUAGGUAAUUUGUGUGGUUGUGCCAGAAACUCAGCCCUUCUAUGUAAUUACAUACAGGAUAAAAGGUAAGUCUGCUCACUUCUCCUUCUACAGGGCAUUUCAACUGACUGGAAUAAGGGCAUGGUUGCAUUUAGUACUCAAUCAGAUAUUACUAGAAAAAAAAUUAAUAAUGUGAGCCUUUCCGAGAGCAGAACGAGGAAAGAUUAAAUUUUAGAAUGCUUCCUUCUGUCUAAUCCAUCAGGGGCCAAAAUGCCCAGUAAAAUUCAAACACAUCACCUAUUAAUAGACUUACAAGUGAGAAAAGAGGUUCCUAGGGUUAUUUUAGGCAAUCCCUGGUAAACUGUUUAAACCAUCAAACCCCUACAGUCAGUUUUCAGUAUCCUCAUUUAAUAUUUUAAUAGGUUUCUUGUGAAUUUAAACUUCUCUUCUUUCUUAAGGUUGUGAAAUUCCAAACUGAUUUUAUGUGAUUUUGAAAAGUUUAGAACCAGUGCUGAGUCUAUGUGGAGGGUUUAUAUUCCUAUGUGAUAUACUGUUAUUAAUGCAUGUGGUGCCAUGCUUGUCUUUAAAUAUAUAAAUAGUGCUAAAUUGCAAAGUCAUAUGGAGCUUUGGAUUUAGUUUGACUUCUUACUACUGCUUUGUCUGCUAUAUUCAAACCCAAAGGCAUUCCCAAGCUAGGGAGAUAAAAAUUAAUUUUCUAAAAUGUCCACAUCCUAUACAUUUUGCUUAUUCAUGGCAUCUUUCAAAUUUUAUUUUAGUUUCCUUUAUUUGCCAAGAAUACAUAUGGAUUUGAAUUUUUAAGGAGAGAAGGAAAGGGUAGGAAACCAGGGCCUUGGGUUUAGUAACAGGCAUUGGAUGUCUAUUAACCAACUAUUCUUACGCUAAUGGCUUUGCAGCUCCUAUUCUCCCAUUUGAUCCUCAAACAAUUCUAUUAGAGUGGUAUUUUUAUCCAAUUUCACAGAUUAAAAUAUAAGCACUCAAUAAAAUAUAACCUUUAGAAGCUUAAAAAGCUAGUAAGUGAUGAACUGAGGAUUUGAACCCAUGUUUGUCACCAAGGAGCUUUCCAGGGCACAUGUCAUAAAAUUAGAGCCAACUGCAGAGCUGUAAGGGAACUUUUAGAGAUGAACUUCUUCAGCCUCCAUAUUUUACAGAAGGAAACUGAAUCCCAGAAGGAGAAAUUGCCGUUCUCAAGGCUCCCUGGAUGGGUAAUAACACAGAUAUGAGUAGGUCACAUAAAGUAUAUCUUUUUUAAAAAAAAGAAAUUCAAUUAUGUCUUAUUUGGGGGGUAUAUUUCCCAGAAGAUAUUUUUCUGGCAUGUGGUCUGUAAACACAGCAUGAUUCAUAUUUUUUAUGUUUCAUGCUACUCAUUUUGUUUAAUUACCAACAAACAUGGGGACUUUGGCUUUUUGACUUAUUUGCAACAAGCAUGAAAUUGUUAAAUUUACCUUUUAUCAAUUGUAAUCAUCCUAUGCCAACAUAUUAUCAUAAAUUCAUAGAAAUAUUUUUAAAAAUAAAUAACAGACAUUGAAAUCCAAUUCUUAGAUAAUACUCCCAGAACAGCCAAUGGUAAAUGCCCUAUACUUGAGUCUUACUUAGAUGCUGUGGUAAUGCACCAUUUUAGAAGAUGAAUGAUACUGCUAUUUCUCUUCAGGGAAACAAUAAUGGAUAAAGAAAUGUAACUGCCGGGCAGCAAAGCUUCUAAGUGAAACCUGUAGUAGCAGUAGUAGUAGGGAGAAAAUGUGUAGUCAUCAAGUGAAAAUAGGAAAGGAUCUAUGAUUUAUGAUGUCUUAAUAGACCCUAAAUUGUUCUUUAAUUACAAGAGUGGCAGUCUCUGAAGUCAUUUGUGAGCUUGUAUGACUUUUGUAUUUAGCAAUGUUGCAUGCUCACAUAAUUGAAAAUUAAAAGUAACACAUUUUUCUGAAAUGUA